AAAGGUAAAAACACCUCCAGAUAAGGAAUAGGAACAGGCUAUGACCUAAUGCUUGCUUGGACCAGUAUAAGCAUGCCAGGGCAAAUAUUUAGGCUAAAAUGUGGGAGCUAAGAACACAAAGUACAUUGAUUUCUUUAUCACGGCUAGCAGAUAUCUAAGAAUGUCAGCACAGGUGUUUGAAUACAUUUUGCUUCUAAGAGAAGUUACUAUUUAUUCCUAAUUACACGAGGAGGAAAGUCCCUUUGAAAAGGAACCUCUAUUUCACAUUUUACGAUGAGCACAAUAUAGUUUUGCAUUGGUGUAUAUGAAUUUGAAUGAGCAAACAGCUCUUCAAGUUUUUGGGGUUUUUUUGUUUGUUUUGUUUUUUGGGUUUUUGUUUUUUGUUUUUGAGACGGAGUCUCACUCUGUCAUCAGGCUGGAGUGCAGUGGCACGAUCUCGGCUCACUGCAACCUCCGCCUCCUGCGUUCAAGUAUUCCCCUGCCUCAGCCUCCCAAGUAGCUGUGACUAAAGCCGUGCACCACAACGUCUGGCCAAUUUUUUGUAUUUUAGUAGAGACGAAGUUUCACCAUAUUGGCCAGGCGAGUCUCAAACUCCUGACCUCGUGAUCCACCCACCUCAGCCUCCCAAAGUGCUUGGAUUAUAGACAUGAGCCUCAGCGCCCAGCCCUCUUCAAGUUUUUAUAAACCAGUUUCAGAAGUUAUGUGUUCUCAUUUUGCCCAAGACCUUUGGCCGGAGCAGAAUAUAAAAGAUUCUUUCCAAAAAGUGACACUGAAAAGAUAUGGAAAAUGUAGACAUGAAAAUUUACCAUUAAGAAAAGGCUGUGAAAGUAUGGAUGAGUGUAAGAUGCACAAAGGAGGUUGUAAUGGACUUAACCAAUGUCUCACAGCUACCCAGAGCAAAAUAUUUCAAUGUGAUAAAUAUGUAAAAGUCGCUCAUAAAUUUUCAAAUUCAAACAGACAUGAGAUAAGACAUACUAAAAAGAAACCUUUCAAAUGUACAAAAUGUGGCAAAUCAUUUGGCAUGAUUUCAUGCCUAACUGAACAUAGCAGAAUUCAUACUAGAGUAAAUUUCUACAAAUGUGAAGAAUGUGGAAAAGCCUUUAACUGGUCCUCAACCCUUACUAAACAUAAGAGAAUUCAUACGGGAGAGAAACCUUACAAAUGUGAAGAAUGUGGUAAAGCCUUUAACCAGUCCUCAAACCUUAUUAAACAUAAGAAAAUUCAUACUGGAGAGAAACCCUACAAAUGUGAAGAAUGUGGCAAAACUUUUAACCGAUUCUCAACUCUUACUACCCAUAAGAUAAUUCAUACUGGAGAGAAACCCUACAAAUGUAAAGAAUGUGGUAAAGCUUUUAACCGAUCUUCAACCCUUACUACCCAUAGAAAAAUUCAUACUGGAGAGAAACCUUACAAAUGUGAAGAAUGUGGCAAAGCCUUUAAGCAGUCCUCAAACCUUACUACACAUAAGAUAAUUCAUACUGGAGAGAAACCCUACAAAUGUAAAAAAUGUGGAAAAGCCUUUAACCAGUCUGCACACCUUACCACACAUGAGGUAAUUCAUACUGGAGAGAAACCCUACAAAUGUGAAAAAUGUGGAAAAGCCUUUAAUCAUUUCUCACACCUUACUACACAUAAGAUAAUUCAUACUGGAGAGAAACCUUACAAAUGUAAAGAAUGUGGUAAAGCUUUUAAACACUCUUCAACCCUUACUAAACAUAAGAUAAUUCAUACUGGAGAGAAGCCUUACAAAUGUAAAGAAUGUGAAAAAGCUUUUAACCAAUCCUCAAAACUUACUGAACAUAAGAAAAUUCAUACUGGAGAGAAACCCUAUGAAUGUGAAAAAUGUGGCAAAGCUUUUAACCAGUCCUCAAAUCUUACUAGACAUAAGAAAAGUCAUACAGAAGAGAAACCUUACAAAUGUGAAGAAUGUGGCAAAGGUUUUAAAUGGCCCUCAACCCUUACUAUCCAUAAGAUAAUUCAUACUGGAGAGAAACCAUACAAAUGUGAAGAAUGUGGCAAAGCUUUUAACCAAUCCUCAAAACUUACCAAACAUAAGAAAAUUCAUACUGGAGAGAAACCCUACACAUGUGAAGAAUGUGGCAAAGCCUUUAACCAGUCCUCAAACCUUACUAAACAUAAGAGAAUUCAUACUGGAGAAAAACCUUACAAAUGUGAAGAAUGUGACAAAGCUUUUAAAUGGUCCUCAGUCCUUACUAAACAUAAGAUAAUUCAUACCGGAGAAAAAUUACAAAUAUGAAAAUUAUGGCAAAGCUUUAAUCAAUUUACAAGUCUUACUAAACAUAAGAAAAUUUAUACUGGAGAGAAACUACUAACCUGAAAGAUGUGACAAUAAUUUUGACAACACCUCAGACUUAUAAAAGUAAUCAUACUGGUGAGAAAUUCUAAAAAUGUGAAGACUAUGGCAAAGUCUUUAAAUGGUUGUCACACUUUAGGUAAGAUAAUUCAUAUUGGAACAAACUACAAGUGCAAACAAUGUGGCAAAACUUAAUUUAUGCUCACACCUUACUGCACAGAAAAGAAUUUUUAGUUGAGAAAAAGUAUACAAAUAUAAAGAAUGUGGAAAAGCCGUUAAUAUCUGCUCACAUCUUACUCAGCAUCAGAAAGUACUUAAUAAAAGCAUUAUAAAUGGAA